AGUCGGAGUCUCACUCUGUCGCCCAGGCUAGAGCGCAGCGGCGCAAUCUCUGCUCAUUGCAAACUCCGCUUCUCGGGUUCAAGCAAUUCAUCUGCCUCAGCCUACCGAAUAGCUGGGAUUACAGGCACGCGCCACCGUGCCCGGCUAAUUUUUGGACUUUUAGUAGAGAUGGGGUUUCACCAUGUUGGCCAGGCUGGUCUCGAAUUCCUGACCUCGUGAUCCACCUGCCUCAUCCUCCCAAAGUGCUGAGAUUACAGGCGUGAACCACCGCGCCCGGCCAGCAGUGGGUCUGUUUUCAACCCUCAUGUACCCUCAGCUCUCAAGCCUGUGUGCUCCCACCCCAGCCAGUCACCAGAAUCACAUAGAUUUUAAAACGACUUAUCCUGGGUCCAUCCCUACACAUAGUAAAUGAGAUUUUUGCUGGGUAGCUUGGGACGCUAUAUUUUCCAAAACUCCCUGUUGAUUGGCUGUAUUUGGGAACCCCUGUUGCGAAGGAAGAUCCCUUAUCUCUUCAUCUGUCACUAAUGAUGGUGGCUUGCGCACUCUGAUGGUACUUACUUGGAUGGGAUUACAGAUGGUUCCAUCACACCCAUCUGUAUGAAAUCUCGUGGUAUAAGUGAAUGUAGGAUGAUAAGGGACGAGCCUAUUAGAGGCUUUUGAAGCAAAUGGAUAGUUUAAUCAGAUUGGUGUGUUUUUUUUUUCUGUAGAACUGCUGUGAACUAGACCUUGUUAUCACCAUCUGUUUCGUAAAUUCCAUUUUCGGUUUAACAGCUGGAUUGUGAAAGAUAUACAAAAUUAUCCAGUUAAAAAACUAAAUUUGGCAAGUGUGUGUGUGUUUUUAAAAAUGACUCCUUGAAUACACUGUUUUGAUUCCUUAGACAGUUUCUAAGGCUCUAAUUUUGGUCUACCAGAAAUAUUCAGAGUAGUAAACUGAGACCAGAAAGGCGAGUUCUUUGGCUUGGAUAACUUUGAGAGUUAAUAGUAUACAUGAUUGGCAGCCUUCAGUUUUAUCCAGCAAUAAAUCUAAACAGUUUAAAAUAAGUACUUUCCCCUUACCUCAGUACAGAGAGGCCCUGGCCACUGCCAUGCACAUCUCAGAAGCUGAGCAGUGGGGCAGAAGGAUAACUUGUAAUUUGGCAUCAAUGUCCAACACCCUUGAGCUCUGGACUCUUUUAUUCAUUCCUUCUACUUUACCAUUCUACAUCUUGAACCACUGUGCGUGCGGUUCCCCUAAGAGGCAGUAAAGUAAUUGCAUCAGGGUGGAGGGAUUUUAUGUGCUUUCACUUUCUCAUUUGAUUAUUUCUACAUCUUACCGAUAAACUUCCAUGAAUAUUACUGUUGUAAUGAGGAGCAAAAUGUUAGUAAAGAUAACUUUAUACGUGAAAACUUGAACUCUUACCAAGAAACGUAGUGUUUGUGACAAGGCUGGCUGAGAGGAUGAGAAUAGCUCAUCAGUACUGGGUUGGCUGAAGGAAACAUGCAUGUCAGUACUAUUUUGAGGGCAGCUGAGAACAUCUAUUUCAAUAGCUUUGGCUAUAUUUUAAUAGCUAAGAGCAACAUAUGAAUUUGUCUCUGCCAAAGAUGGAGUGAAAAUUUCCAAAAUAACCAAACUUUUACUUUUUUUGCAAUACAUUAGGUCUUUCCUGCUGACAAACCUACAGUUUAUGAAAUAAGUUUGUGGAGCAUAUCAAAGCUGUGCGGCAGCUCUGUGCACUCCAGCAGAUGGUGUGACUGGUUGUCUGUAGUCGUCUUAGUUUCCGCCAUUGUGUCAGUCUGUGGAAUGUUUGGGUUCAUGCUUAUUUUGGCCAAGUUUUCCAAAUUCUGUCUUGAUGUCCUAAACGAUGCUAUAUUUGAUGAAGAUCAUGAUGAGAUGGUGAUUGUGAAGGACAUAGACAUGUUUUCCAUGUGUGAGCAUCACUUGGUUCCAUUUGUUGGAAAGGUCCAUAUUGGUUAUCUUCCUAACAAGCAAGUCCUUGGCCUCAGCAAACUUGCGAGGAUUGUAGAAAUCUAUAGUAGAAGACUACAAGUUCAGGAGCGCCUUACAAAACAAAUUGCUGUAGCAAUCACGGAAGCCUUGCGGCCUGCUGGAGUCGGGGUAGUGGUUGAAGCAACACACAUGUGUAUGGUAAUGCGAGGUGUACAGAAAAUGAACAGCAAAACUGUGACCAGCACAAUGUUGGGUGUGUUCCGGGAGGAUCCAAAGACUCGGGAAGAGUUCCUGACUCUCAUUAGGAGCUGAGCUUCAUUCAGUGUGUGUGCGUUGGUUGCCGAUCGUACUGCCAGUAGCAUUGUCUGUCUGUCCGGUCUUGUUUGUACAUUCCAUUUUCAAUUGUUACAGAUGUGAACUUUAUUCCUUGUCACUAAUUAUAUUUAAAAUUAUUUCUAGGAAGUCAAAUAAAUAUAAUAAAGGGUUGAGCCCUCUACUUUCUUCUUGCCACCUUUUUGUGGCAAUAUUAAAGUGAACUGCUAAUAGUGUAAGUACGUGCACAAAACCACUGCCAGAUAACCAGAGGGGCCUGGGAAGGGAGAAGAAUUAGUGUAUUUUUUUCAAAUAGUACAGUAAUUUGCCUCAUAAGCAUAGGAGCAUUGGGAAUGAGAGGGAACUGUGCCCAGUAUACUGUUUUUUUUCUUCCUCCAAUAAAAGUGGUGUAGUGCCGAAAGUGCUAAAAUAUUUAGUGCGGUAUUGCUCUGUGAAUUCAAGUUCAACAGACUUCACUUUGGUCAUGUUUAUUAAACCACCAGUGACAUUUAAAAAUAUAUUUUUAGCAGUCGUAAUGUUAGUCACCAAGGGAAGGUGGUGGAAUGUCUAUGUUUUUGAUUUUACUGUGAGUUAAAAAGGCACAUUUCUACCUUCUAUUGUUUUUAAAUUCAAGAAUAGGGAAUUAGUUCCUGGUGUUGUUUACGAGUGUAUUCUCGUGUCAACAUACAGGGAUUUAGACAUUUAACUCUCUGUGCCUUGAUAAGAAUAUCAUUUAGAGUGUAGAUACUUUUGCCUUUUUAAAAAAGCCAUUAUUUUAUGAGACUUAGUACUCACACUGCAAAUAACUAGUCAGCUCAGUUUUAACUUUAUAGGUUUAUUGAGUUUCCUUUGUGUGAUCCAUGUAGAUGCCUCAAAAUGUUUCUUCUUCUUCUUUUUUUUAAUCUUAUAAGAUAUUUUUCUAAGUAUUUCCAGAAACAUUUGAGAGUGCCCAUCAUUUUCAGGUCUGCAGAACCAUAGCUUCCACGCACCUGAACGAGCACAGAAUGAACUGACGGUGGAAGACAUUAUGAGCUGUGUCCAACGUUUUAACCAAAGCGUAUCGUACCAACGAUCUGUGAAAAUGCACUGGAAGCUUCUGGUCCCGGUUUCCUUUGUGGUCUAUGUGGGUCUUGUCCUCAUUGUAACUCCGUAUAGAUGGUAUAGGUAUUUUAAUCCUGGAAGCUGUUGCCUUAUUAAUGAUUAUCUUAAAAUUUCCUCCAUUGGGGCAGCGUGGGCCAAAUUAAAACAAACAAAACCGCAACUCCUCCACAGAAACACAAACACAGUUAUUCCAUGAAGUUUAGUAUUUGGUUGACAUAGUGCUCUUCAAAUUCAUCCCAUUACCCUAAAAGUAAUAACUUUGAUGCUUGCUUUAACUUUAGUCCCAUCUCUGCCACUUUGAUGCUAUUUGGGUUAUGAUGGGGCAAGAUGGCAGAGGUAUUGGGUUUUUUUGUUUUUUUCCAUUCCUCUCUACUUCUGUUUCCUAGCUUUUUCUUUCUGGAGUUUAAGUACAGUGAUGGUUGGCUUGAGUACCUUUUUAAAUCUAGCCCAGUAUAAACAUUAGCCUGCUUAAUAUUUAGACAUUUAUAGGUAGAAUUCUGAGCACUCAACUCAUGUUUGGCAUUUUAAAGUAAAAACAAGUGUGACUUCGAGGACCAAAGAAAUUGUCAGCUAUACAUUUAUCUUUAUGAACUCAUUUAUAUUCCUUUUUAAUGACUCGUUGUUCUAACAUUUCCUAGAAGUGUUCUUAUAAAGGUCUAAUGUAUCCACAGGCUGUUGUCUUAUUAGUAAAUGCAAAGUAAUGACUUUGUCUGUUUUACUCUAGUCUUUAGUACUUCAAAAUUACCUUUUCAUAUCCAUGAUCUUGAGUCCAUUUGGGGGAUUUUUAAGAAUUUGAUGUAUUUCAAUACACUGUUCAAAAUUAAAUUGUUUAAUUUUAUGUAUGAGUAUGUAUGUUCCUGAAGGUGGUCCUAUUUAAAUUAUUAAACUAUUGUAACUUU